AGAGCUUCCGGGCUGCGCUCUUCGUUGCCCAGUUUCCGCUCAGUGGUCGCGUCUCCGCCCCCCACCCACCAGUCCCGCUGCAUUCUCGGCCGGGCUCUAGGCGCCAUGGCUCCCCGCGGGAGGAAGCGUAAGGCUGAGGCCGCGGUGGUCGCCGUAGCCGAGAAGCGAGAGAAGCUGGCGAACGGCGGGGAGGGAAUGGAGGAGGCGACCGUUGUUAUCGAGCAUUGCACUAGCUGACGCGUCUAUGGGCGCAACGCCGCGGCCCUGAGCCAGGCGCUGCGCCUGGAGGCCCCAGAGCUUCCAGUAAAGGUGAACCCGACGAAGCCCCGGAGGGGCAGCUUCGAGGUGACGCUGCUGCGCCCGGACGGCAGCAGUGCGGAGCUCUGGACUGGGAUUAAGAAGGGGCCCCCACGCAAACUCAAAUUCCCUGAGCCUCAAGAGGUGGUGGAAGAGUUGAAGAAGUACCUGUCGUAGGGAGAUUUGGGUAGAAGCCCUCAUGCUGAGCUUUGUGUCCCUGGUGAUGUUGGAACAUUAAUGAUGGAACAUGGCCAAACUUCAGUCAUGAUCCUGAAGCCAUGGUUUCUUCCCUGCCAGAAAUGAAGGUUCAGUUAUGAGGCAACCCUCUAGUAAGGCAUUGUAAAAGUUACUGGAUUUGGUUUAAUAAAAGUUGAAAUAAAGUAUUUGAGUAAUAGAGUAAAACUUAAUCUUAAGGGAUGGACAAAGCCAGCCUUGUGGAGUUGGUAGUCCUUGUGUUUUUCAUAGCCCAAGAUAGCCAUGUGACCUGGAACUUUUAAAAAAAAAUUUUUUUUUAAGAGCCAGAGUCUCACUUUGUCACCCAUGCUGGAGUAUAGUGGUGCUAUCUCGGCUCACUGCAACCAUUGUCUCCCAGGUUCAAGCGAUACUCCUGCCUCAGUCUCCUGAGUAGCUGGGAUCACAGGUGCACACCACCACGCCUGGCUAAUUUUUUUAUUUUUAUUUUUAGUAAAGGCGGGGUUUCACCAUGUUGGCCAGGCUGGUCUCAAACUCCUGACCUCAAGUGAUAUGCCUGCCUUGACCUCCCAAAGUGCUGGGGUUACAGGCAUGAUGAGCCACCGCACCUGGCCUGACCUGCAACUUUUAUGAUCUCUGGUAAAACAUGAGAAAUACUUGUAAAAAUUAUGGGAGCAAAGUAAAUAAUUUAUUUUUUAAAAAA